CCCAACUAACAUCUGGAUUGAACAAUGCCAGACACGAGAUACAGUGCUGCUCCAGUACCUCCAGCUCCAAUGAAUACAAAGAGGGAGAUCAAGCUUAGAUGCUUCUUGGACUGAGUGAUGAUGUGGUGGAGCAUGUUUGCUGAAGAGGCCUCCGAUUGGAAAGGAGAGAACCAGCCUAGCCACCAGGCUCUGGCCUAAGUAGUAUCUCCAUAGUGUUUCUUGAUAGGUUCUGUUUCUACCACUUUACUCUUCUAAUUAACAGAUAUCUGGUGAAUGACAAAUAUGGGCCAGACACUCUUCUGGGCAUUAGGGACAAAACAUUUUGCAAAUUGGGCAAAAAUUUCUGCCCUCCUGGGACUUGCAUUCAAGUGGGAGGAGAGAGAAAAGGAAAUGCAUAAUUAGCUAAAAUAUAUAUAGUAUGUUCAAAGGUGUUAAGUGCUAUGGAGAAAAAUAAGGCAGGGCAGGAGGAAAGGGAGUGCUAUGGCUGAGAUAUGGUGUGAUAUUAAAUUGGCUUUGCAGUAUUAUCUAAACAAGAGGAGGGUGAAGGCUUGGACCAGAGGAGUAGUGAUAGAAAUGGUGAAAAGUGGUUGCAAUCUGGGUAAAUUUCAGCAAGGCCUAAAGAAGGUGAAGGAUUGAGCCCUGCAGAUACCAGGAAGAUGAGAAUUCCAGACAGAGCUGUUGCAAAUGCAAAAGCAGGAGUGAACCUGGGGUGCCAAGAAACCACUCUAACAGGGGCAUCCGAUCUUUUGGCCUCCCUGGGACACACUUGAAGAAGAAGAAUUGUCUUGGGCCACACAUAAAAUACAUUAAUGAUAGCUGAUGAGCUAAAAGAAAAAAAAUCACAAAAUCUCAUAAUGUUUUAGGAAAGGAAAGCUUGCAAAUUUCUGUUGGGUCAUAUUCAAAGCCAUCCUGGGCCACAAGUGGUCUGCAGGCCACAGAUUGGACAAGCUUGUGCUAGAAGGCCCAGUGUGGCUGGAGCAAAGCGAGUGUGCAGGAGAGGGCUAUGAGACUGGUGUGGGGUGGGAGUGAGAUUGCAGAGGGCCUUUUAGGACUUUUGUAAAGAUUUUCGCUUUUUCACAGAGUGAGAUGGAGAAUUAUUAGAGGAUUUUGAAUGGAGAAGAAACCCAGGAUCAUUCUGGUUGCUCACUUGAGAUGACUCUCUAGGGGUCAUUGGUAGAAGUGGAGAGACUAAUCAGGAAGAUAUUGCAAUAAUCUUGCAAUAAUCUAAUUGAGAGAUGAUGGUGGCUUGGAUCGGGGUAGCAGCUAAGAUGGGUCAGAAAUCGUUGGAAUCUGAAUAUAUUUUUGUAGGUAAAACUUUUUGCCCUUAUGUCUAUGUAAUAUUUUUUGAUAUUCCUCUUAAAAUAGAGCCCUAAACUCCAGUAAGGGACCUGAAUAAUGCUAGUUAUAGCAAAAGGUUAACUGUCUGACUCUUGAAUACCACAAAUUUAGUAUUGUGUUUUCAGCCCCCGCCAUGGGGUAGAUAUUAUUUUCCUAUGUUUCUUUUUUUUAAUUAUUAUACUUUAAGUUCUGGGAUACGUGUGCAGAACCUGCAGGUUUGUUACAUAGGUAUACACGUGCCAUGGUGCUUUGCUGUGCCCAUCAACCCGUCGUCUACAUUGGGUAUUUCUCCUAAUGCUAUCCCUUCCCCAGCCUCCCAUCCCCUGACAGGUCCCAGUGUGUGAUGUUCCCCUCCCUGUGUCCAUGUGUUCUCAUUGUUCAACUCCCACUUAUGAGUGAGAACAUGCAGUGUUUGGUUUUCUGUUCUUGUGUUAGUUUGCUGAGAAUUAUGGUUUCUAGCUUCAUCCAUGUCCCUGCAAAGGACAUGAACUCAGCCUUUUUUAUGGCUACAUAGUAUUCCAUGGUGUAUAUGUGCCACAUUUUCUUUAUCCAGUCUAUCAUUGAUGGGCAUUUGGGUUGGUUCUAAGUCUUUGCUAUUGUGAAGAGUGCUGCAAUAAACACACAUGUGGCCGGACGCGGUGGCUCAUGCCUGUAAUCCCAGCACUUUGGGAGGCAGAGGCGGGCGGAUCAUGAGGUCAGGAGAUCGAGACCAUCCUGGCUAACACAGUGAAACCCCACCUCUACUAAAAAUACAAAAAAUUAGCCGGGCUUGGUGGCCAGCACCUGUAGUCCUAGCUACUCGGGAGGCUGAGGCAGGAGAAUGGUGUGAACCCGGGAGGCAGAGCUUGCAGUGAGCCGAGAUUGCGCCACUGCACUCCAGCCUGGGCGACAGAGCGAGACUCUGUCUCAAAAAAAAAAAAAAAAAUACAUGUGCAUGUGUCUUUAUAGUAGAAUGAUUUAUAAUCCUUUGGGCAUAGACCCAGUAAUGGGAUUGCUGGGUCAAAUGGUGUUUCCAGUUCCAGAUCCUUGAGGAAUUGUCACACUGUCUUCCACAAUGGUUGAACUAAUUUACACUCCCACCAACAGUGUAAAAGCGUUCCUGUUUCUCCACAUCCUCUCCAGCAUCUGUUGUUUCCUGACUUUUAAUGAUCGCCAUUCUAACUGGUGUGAGAUGGUAUCUCAUUGUGGUUUUUAUUUGCAUUUCUCUGAUGACCAGUGAUGAUGAGCUUUUUUUCAUGUUUGUUGGCUGCAUAAAUGUCUUCGUUUAAGAAGUGUCUGUUCAUAUCCUCUGCCCACUUUUUGAUGGUGUUGAUUUUUUUCUUGUAAACUUGUUUAAGUUCUUUGUAGAUUCUGGAUAUUAGCCCUUUGUCAGAUGAAUAGAUUGCAAAAAAUUUCUCCCAUUCUGUAGGUUGCCUGUUCACCCUGAUAACAGUUUUGUUUGUUUGUUUGUUUGUUUUUUGCUGUGCAAAAGCUCUUUAGUUUAAUUAUAUCCCAUUUGUCAAUUUUGGCUUUUGUUGCCAUUGCUUUUGGUGUUUUAGUCAUGAAGUCUUUGCCCAUGCCUAUGUCCUGAAUGGUAUUGUCUAGAUUUUCUUCUAGGGUUUUUAUGGUUUUAUGUCUUACAGUUAAGUCUUUAAUCUAUCUUGAGUUAAUUUUUGUAUAAUGUGUAAGGAAGGGGUGCAGUUUCAGUUUUCUGCAUACGGCUAGCCAGUUUUCCCAACAUCAUUUACUAAAUAGGGAACCCUUUCCCCAUUUCUUAUUUUUGUCAGGUUUGUCAAAGAUCAGAUGGUUGUAGAGGUGUGGUGGUAUUUCUGAGGCCUCUAUUCUGUUCCAUUGGUCUAUAUUUGUGUUUUGGUACCAGUACCAUGCUGUUUUGAUUACUGUAGCCUUGUAGUAUAGUUUGAAGUCAGGUAGUGUGAUGCCUCCAGCUUUGUUCUUUUUGCUAAGGAUUGUCUUGGCUAUGUGAGCUCUUUUUUGGUUCCAUAUGAAAUUUAAAGCAGUUUUUUCUAAUUACGUGAAGAAAGUCAAUGGUAGCUUGACAGUGAUAGCAUUGAAUCUAUAAAAUUACUUUGGGCAGUAUGGCCAUUUUCACGAUAUUGAUUCUUUCUAUCCAUGAGCAUGGAAUGUUUUUCCAUUUGUUUGUGUUCUCUCUUAUUUCCUUGAGCAGUGGUUUGUAGUUCUCCUUGAAGAGAUCCUUCACAUCCCUUGCAAGUUGUGUUCCUAGGUAUUUUAUUCUCUUUGUAGUAAUUGUGAAUGGGAUUUCACUCAUGAUUUGGCUGUUUGUCUAUUAUUGCUGUAUAGGAAUGCUUGUGAUUUUUACACAUUGAUUUUGUAUCCUGAGACUUUGCUGAAGUUGCUUAUCAGCUUAAGGAGAUGAUGAUGGGGUUUUCUAAAUAUACAAUCAUGUCAUCUGCAAACAGAGACAAUUUGACUUCCUCUCUUCCUAUUUGAAUAUCCUUUAUUUCUUUCUCUUGCCUGAUUGCCCUGGCCAGAACUUCCGAUACUACGUUGAAUAGGAGUGGUGAGAGAGGGUAUCCUUGUCUUGUGCCAGUUUUCAAAGGGAAUGCUUCCAGCUUUUGCCCGUUCAUUAUGAUAUUGGCUGUGGGUUUGUCAUAAAUAGCUCUUAUUAUUUUGAGAUACAUUCCAUUAAUACCUAGUUUAUUGAGAGUUUUUAGCAUGAAAGGGUGUUGAAUUUUGUUGAAGGCCUUUUCUGCAUCUAUUGAGAUAAUCAUGUGGUUUUUGUCAUUGGUUCUGUUUAUGUGAUGGAUUAUGUUUAUUGAUUUGUGUAUGUGUAGGCCUAGGUUAAUAUACAUGUUGGCGUCUUCGUUUUUAGUUAAAAAAUUUAAAAAGCAAAAUAUAAUAAUUUAAUAGCAAAAAACUUAUUGAAUAAGGAAUAAAAUAUAUUUUUGCGCAGCUAUAAAAUGUGUUUGUGUUUUAAGCCAAAUGUUAUUAUGAAAGCAUCAAAAAGUUAUAAAGAAUGUUUAAAGUUUAAAAAGCAAAAAAGUUGCAGUAACCUACAGCUUAUUGUUGAAGAAAGAAAAAUUUUUUUUAUAAAUUUAGUGUAGCCUAGGUGUACAGUGUUUAUUAUAAAGUCUACGGCAGUGCAAAGUAACAUCCUAGGCCCUCACAUUCACUCAUCACUCACUUGCUGACCCAUCCAGAGCAACUUCCAGUCCUGCAAACUCCAUUCAUGGUAAGUACCCUAUACAGGUGUACUAUUUUUAAUCUUUUAUACAUUUUUAUUUUACCUUUCCUAUGUUUCGAUACACAAAUACUUACUAUUAUGUUGCAGUUACCUACAGGAUUCAGUACAGGAAAAUGCUGUACAGAUUUAUAGCCUAGGAGCAAGAGGCCAAACCCUAUAGCCAAAGUGCGUAGUAGGCUAUACCGUCUAGGAUUGUAUAAGUACACUCUAUGACAUCCACACGACAAAAUUGCCUAAUGAUGCGUUUCUCAGAACGUAUCCCCAUUAUUAAGCAACAUAUGACUGCAUUUUGACCCAAAUGAUCAAUGAUUGCUAUUGCACUGCUGUUGCUUAAUAAACAUGUACAUUCCCUUCUUGCAGUCUUUACCUUAUUCCAUGGUAGGUCCCUGGAAGUUGACAGAGGCCGGCAAUGUGAGUAGAGGAAAAAACAUGAUACUGUUAAUAAUAUAAAGGAGACGAGUUAACGGGUGCAGCACACCAACAUGGCACACGUAUACAUAUGUAACAAACCUGCACCUUGUGCACAUGUACACUAGAACUUUAACAAAAAUAUAUAUAUAUAAAGAAGCCCAUGAUUCAAAACAAAUGAGGCCCAGGACAGUUCUUGUCCCACUCCUCUCCUUUGUUCCUUCUCCCAACUCUCUAAAUAAGAUAGAAUUGUCCUUUUCCAGCUCCAUGCAGAUCUCUCAGGUGGCCUCUUUGACUUCUUUGCUUCCUCUUUGCCCCUAAACAGGGUGCAGGUAUCAUGAGAAAAUGCAGAGUAGUACAAAAGAAAUCUGGUGUUCUCUUCCCCAAAACCAAGUGCACCUUACUCUAAUUUCUGUUAGUCACAUAAACAUUUCUGUUAUUCAUUUUAAUAACUGGAAGAAUUUCAGGUUAAGUAGAUGCUCAUUUCUCAUUUCAUUGGUUCAGCAAUUACUUAUUGAGUACCUUUUAUGUGCCAGAUACUGUUCUAGGCUCUGGGAGACAGGAGUGAACAAAACAAAGUCCCCAUUUCUUAGGGAGCUUACCUUAUGAUGCAGCAGAGAGAUAGAAGUAUAACUAAAUGAGUAAUACCCGUAUAGUACAUCUGAUAAAGAUAAUGCUAUUGAGGAAAGCAACUUAGGGAAUGAAAAAGGGAGUGCUGGGAUGGCAUGCUCUUGCUUUUGGUGAGUUGGUAUUAAUAUUUUCAAUAGGGUAGCCAGAAAAGGUGUCUCCAAUAAUGAUAUAUGUGCAGAGACCUGAAGGAAGUGAGAAAACAAUAUUCAUGCCAAUAUCUGGUGGCAGAAUGCUCCUUGCUGCAGGAAGUCCUUAGACCGUUUUCUCCUCUCUAUAUGCUGCCUAGGUGGUUUCAUCCUAUCACUUUUUAUAACCCUAAUGACUCCCAAACUUCUAUCUCUAUCCCAGAUCUUUCCUAUCUCUAGUCCAGUGUAUCCAGCUGUUUGUGGAGCCCCUCCACUUGGGUGUCUAGUAGACAUCUCAGAUUUCAGAUGUCUCUAUCCAAACUCCUUAUUCCCCACUCCCUAAACCUACUUUCUGUAGCCUCUCACUCCCUUUAUAAAAUGGCAACUCCAUUAUUUCAGCUUCUCAACUUAAAAAUAUUGGACUCAUAAUGAUUCUUCUCUCUCAAACCUCACACCCAAUCCAUCAGCUAGAGCACGAGUUACUUAUAUUGGGAAAAACUAAAAAAGGAGUAAACCUAGGGCAGUGGGAGGAAGAAAUUAAGGUAAAAUACAAAGCAGAGCAGUAAUAGAGCUACUUUCUGGGCAGUGUUUGAUGGGAUGAGGAAAAUCUAAGCUGAAGGCAUUUGAGCCUUGGAACUCAGGUUGCUGGGAAAUCACAUCCUAAGCCACAUUCCCUUAAAAGAGCUAAAACUUUAAAGUGGUUUGCUAUGUUUUGAUAUGUCUUAACAUCAAGAGUGAGUUAGUUGGCAAAACUCAAGCUGUCAACCCAUGGGUUAGAAAGAGACUUUAGGUACCCGUGAGAAUGUUUUACAUAAAGUUUACCUAAAGUAUUUUCCAUUUCCUGCUUCUGGAAACAUUGUGGGACCUGAAUGGAGAAGCCAGAAGUGCAAAGUCAUAAUAAUAAUUUUAAAAAACAGUGAGCAUUUGAACCAGUCUUAGAAAAAUGAAUGUUCUUUGUUGGCAUAUCUACAAUAAAGCAAAACACUUAGCUGAAACAUCAGGGAAAGGAAAUGAUAAAUGUCAUGGGGUAAAAGAUGGUUAAAUACUUAAGUAUCUUGAUUAUAUUAAUUUGAACCAUGAAAAGGAAGUAAGUACUCACUGUCCUUCUGUUUUGAUUUGGUAUACAUUUCCCAGCAUUCAAAUUCUCAGCACAGAAGGUUCUUGCUGUUUUGCUGCACCAAGUUCUUGGAAAUCACAUACAGAUCCCCCUAAAGGAGAUUGGAACAGUGCAAUAUUUGGGGACUGCAUUCUCCACCCAAGGAUUUAGCAUCAAAUGAAAAACAGAAACAUGAUUCCCGUGACAGAAUUCCGGCAGUUCUCUGAGCAGCAGCCUGCCUUCCGAGUGCUGAAGCCAUGGUGGGAUGUGUUUACCGAUUACCUCUCAGUAGCCAUGCUCAUGAUCGGCGUGUUUGGAUGUACUUUACAGGUCAUGCAAGACAAGAUAAUCUGCCUUCCGAAAAGAGUGCAGCCUGCUCAGAACCACUCUUCCCUUUCGAAUGUCUCUCAAGCAGUUGCCAGUACCACUCCACUGCCUCCACCUAAACCAUCUCCUGCUAACCCCAUCACUGUGGAAAUGAAAGGCCUGAAGACAGAUUUGGACCUUCAGCAGUACAGCUUUAUAAAUCAGAUGUGUUAUGAGCGAGCCCUCCACUGGUAUGCCAAGUAUUUCCCUUACCUUGUCCUCAUCCAUACCCUGGUCUUUAUGCUCUGCAGUAACUUUUGGUUCAAAUUCCCUGGUUCCAGCUCCAAAAUAGAACAUUUCAUCUCCAUUCUGGGGAAGUGUUUUGACUCUCCUUGGACCACACGGGCUUUAUCUGAAGUGUCUGGGGAGGACUCAGAAGAAAAGGACAACAGGAAGAACAACAUGAACAGGUCCAACACCAUCCAAUCUGGUCCAGAAGACAGCCUGGUCAACUCUCAGUCUUUAAAGUCCAUUCCUGAGAAGUUUGUAGUUGAUAAAUCCACUGCAGGGGCUCUGGAUAAAAAGGAAGGUGAGCAGGCUAAGGCCUUAUUUGAGAAGGUGAAGAAGUUCAGGCUGCAUGUGGAAGAAGGUGAUAUUCUAUAUGCCAUGUAUGUUCGCCAGACUGUACUUAAAGUUAUCAAAUUCCUAAUCAUCAUUGCAUAUAAUAGUGCUCUGGUUUCCAAGGUCCAGUUUACAGUGGACUGUAAUGUGGACAUUCAGGACAUGACUGGAUAUAAAAACUUUUCUUGCAAUCAUACCAUGGCACACUUGUUCUCAAAACUGUCCUUUUGCUAUCUGUGCUUUGUUAGUAUCUAUGGAUUGACGUGCCUUUAUACCUUAUACUGGCUGUUCUACCGUUCUCUACGGGAAUAUUCCUUUGAGUAUGUCCGUCAGGAGACUGGAAUUGAUGAUAUUCCAGAUGUGAAAAAUGACUUUGCUUUUAUGCUUCAUAUGAUAGAUCAGUAUGACCCUCUCUAUUCCAAGAGAUUUGCAGUGUUCCUGUCUGAAGUCAGUGAAAACAAAUUAAAGCAGCUGAACUUAAAUAACGAAUGGACUCCUGAUAAACUGAGGCAGAAGCUACAGACAAAUGCCCAUAAUCGACUGGAAUUGCCUCUUAUCAUGCUCUCUGGCCUUCCAGACACUGUUUUUGAAAUCACAGAGUUGCAAUCUCUAAAACUUGAAAUCAUUAAGAACGUAAUGAUACCAGCCACCAUUGCACAGCUAGACAAUCUUCAAGAGCUCUCUCUGCACCAGUGUUCUGUCAAAAUCCACAGUGCGGCGCUCUCUUUCCUGAAGGAAAACCUCAAGGUCUUGAGCGUCAAGUUUGAUGACAUGAGGGAACUCCCCCCCUGGAUGUAUGGGCUCCGAAAUCUGGAAGAGCUGUACCUAGUUGGCUCUCUAAGUCAUGAUAUUUCCAGAAAUGUCACCCUUGAGUCUCUGCGGGAUCUCAAAAGCCUUAAAAUUCUCUCUAUCAAAAGCAACGUUUCCAAAAUCCCUCAGGCAGUGGUUGAUGUUUCCAGCCAUCUCCAGAAGAUGUGCAUACAUAAUGAUGGCACCAAGCUGGUGAUGCUCAACAACUUAAAGAAGAUGACCAAUCUGACAGAGCUGGAGCUGGUCCACUGUGACCUGGAGCGUAUUCCUCAUGCUGUGUUCAGCCUACUCAGCCUCCAGGAAUUGGACCUGAAGGAAAACAAUCUGAAAUCUAUAGAAGAAAUCGUUAGCUUUCAGCACUUAAGAAAGUUGACAGUGCUAAAACUGUGGCAUAACAGCAUCACCUACAUCCCAGAGCAUAUAAAGAAACUCACCAGCCUGGAACGCCUGUCCUUUAGUCACAAUAAAAUAGAGGUGCUGCCUUCCCACCUCUUCCUAUGCAACAAGAUCCGAUACUUGGACUUAUCGUACAAUGACAUUCGAUUUAUCCCCCCUGAAAUUGGAGUUCUACAAAGUUUACAGUAUUUUUCCAUCACAUGUAACAAAGUGGAAAGCCUUCCAGAUGAACUCUACUUCUGCAAGAAACUUAAAACUCUGAAGAUUGGAAAAAACAGCCUAUCUGUACUUUCACCGAAAAUUGGAAAUUUGCUAUUUCUUUCCUACUUAGAUGUAAAAGGUAAUCACUUUGAAAUCCUCCCUCCUGAACUGGGUGACUGUCGGGCUCUGAAGCGAGCUGGUUUAGUUGUAGAAGAUGCUCUGUUUGAAACUCUGCCUUCUGACGUCCGGGAGCAAAUGAAAACAGAAUAACUUAUUUUUCGUUAAAGUUUGACUGAAACACGCUUCUACCAAAUACAGUAUAAAUAAUUAGGUAGUCUUAAUGCCUUUCCUAUUUUUUUUUCCUUUUCACACAAAAUGUACACAAAGAUCGCGUAAGGAGUAUGUAUUUUUAAUAAAAAUUUAAUUGUAUUUUUUCAAUAUUAAUAUUUUGAAGUUUUAUUUGUCUUGAAACACAAUGUAUCUAUUAUCUACUGACAGAAAGAGAUAGUUCCAUUUGGUUUUUUGUUUUUGUUUUUUAGUUCAUUCUUGUGGAAAGGAGGGAAUUAUAAGUUGCAUGCUUUUUGGCAUUUUUUAAAUAGAGGAAGAUAUUUUGCCAAGGCCAUUUUUAACUUGUUUACACCUGUACAGGGUUCUUAUUUUUGUUUUCAUUGUGUGUGUAUCAAGGAAUCUGUGCUAGUUAUUUUAAUACCAGCUGUCUUCUCCAUUGGCCAAGACCUUCAUUCAGUGGAACUUCACAUAAGUGCAUUGUCAUAGAGUAUUUUAAAUGUUCCCCUGCCUCCAACAAAACCCUAAACUGUGUUAUUUCAUAUACCUGACAGUUAUUGUUAUCCUUAGGCAAGGUUUUUGUGAGUGAAGAAAAUAAUCUUUAGUGGCUGGUAUGUUUGAAUUAGGCCUUUAUCAUUUAACUUAUUUGCAUUUUACCAACAUUUUAAAAAUAUUUAAAACCUAAAUACAGAGGCUCCUCCCACCUUAAUCUCAAUACUGCUAUGUAGUACUGGUGAACAACUUUGGAGAACCUAGAUUUAUUUUAAUAUUCUAAUAGAUAAUUAAAUUUUAAAAUGAUAGAAGCCUGGUUUUUGAGUAAUUUAAUCAUCUUUCAUAUCUUGAUAUGCAGCUGCAUCAGAUGGAAAAAAAUUUACUAAAGCACCCUGUUAAAGAGCUGGUGUGCUCCAGUGAGGCCCUCUCCUUUUCUCAGCACAGUGUGGCAGUGGUAAUCUAUUCAAAUUUUGCCUGUUACACAAAAUAAUCCACUUAUAUAUACAGUCAGCCUUCCGUACUUGUGGGUUCUGCAUCUGUGGAUUCCACCAACUGUAGAUGGAAAAUACUCAAAAAGAAAGUUGUGUCUGUACUGAAUAUGUACAGACUUUUUCCUUGUCAUUAUUCCCUAAACAAUACAGCGUAACAACUAUUUAAAUAGGAUUUACAUUGUUUUAGGUAUUAUAAAUUACCUAGAGAUGAUUUAAAGUAUAUGGGAGGAUGUGCAUAGGUUAUAUGCAAUUUCUGCACCAUUUUAUGUCAAGGAUUUUGAACAUCCUCAGAUUUUGGUGUUCGAGGGCAUCCUGGAAUCAAUUCCCCAUGAUACCGAGGGAUGACUGGAUAUUAAUCGAUUUCCCUCAAGCCUGCCCUUGCUGUGAACUAGUGCUACAAGCACGGGAAAUCCAUCUGCUCUCUGGCUUAAAAUAUGUAUCUCAUCUAAAAUUGUUCGUUAAAGUGUGAAUAAAUUGCUAAGUGGUUGUUGCUUAGCAAUAAUUUUUGCCUGACCAUCAGCAGAGCUUUUAUUUACCUUUGUAAUUAAAAUCCAACAUAGCAUGGGCUCUUGGGCAAAAUAUUUCACUGACUAUUAAGCAUGUAGAACAGGAAAAUGAAAUACACUAUUUGUGCCCUUGACCUAGAACCAGAACCACUAAUUAUGAGAACUUUGUUUUAUGUACCAAAUUCACAUUGACCAUUUUCUGAGCUCUAGACUGAUCGUAGUAAGUUUUGUGACUUAACAAUGAAAGAAAGUAGAAAGAUGCUUUGGGUUUUCAAAAUGUUGUUUUUUAAAAUUGUUCUUUGGGUGAAUUUACUCAGUGCUGCUUUGAGUUGUAUACAGAAACAAAUGUUGGGAAUUGCUCCUCAGAAAUGUGUUCCUAAGUUGUGUUUUCAACUUUACAUCAUGAGGUGAAGCAUUAGGGAAAGAGAUUCUUUCGAUUUGUUUAAUAAUCUAAUUAUACAGACCAAAGUGCUUUACGUUUCUGCUCUAUGUUAAUGUUUUAGAAUGGUGAUUUUGCUGAUUAAUUUAGACCUGGAAUUGAAAUAAUGUGCUCAGAAUAAUAACAUGGUUAUAGUUCUUGUAUGAUAAAGUAUUCAAUUUCAGAAUAGUGUUGGAAUCCUGAGUUUGAAUAAUGUGUUGUAUUUAGAAACAUAGCCCUAUCUGUUUUAAACAAAUAAUUUGUUGGCCGAUUGUCCAUGGUUGAGCAUGACAAAAAUACCUCGUCGAAAGGCAAGCUUAGGUAACUGCUGGCAAAACACUGGGUGCACUAUUUUUCUGGAUAAAAUUUAUAGUUAUUUUCUAUAUUACCCUUCAAAAGGGAUCUCUUCAGGUUAAAAAUCACGCUUAUGCUGAAGUCUUUAUCUGGUGUUAACUAAAAAUCUCAUAUGGGUUCAUAACCGAGGUCACUAAUAAUUCAUUUUUAUCACUUGUAAAAAUUUGCUCAAAAUUCCAAAAAAAUAUUGAUUUGUUUUUUAGUGAUUUUGCAGGCUGACCCCCAACCUAAGUUUUGAUAACAUCUGGUAAGUCAGUAUAGUUCUGUGACUUCAUGUUUUAACUAAGAAGGAAAAUUCAUAGAUAUUCCUAUUAGAUUUUAUAAACCUUCAAAAGUCUGAAACUUAAUUUUGAGUCUAAAUUUUCUGACACUGGCCCCUUUUAAUAUUGUAAGUUUUUGUUCACUUUCUUAAGUAAAAAAAACAUUUAAUUACUAGUUAGCCCUUAACUGGGAAACUCAGGUAAUGAACUGCUGACUUUUCUAAAGUUCUUUAACUGAUCAAUUCUGUAUAGAGGGAUAUUUAUCUAACCACUUUCCGUAUUUUACAAGUGCUCUUUCUAAAAAGGAAUAACUAUUAUAGCUCUAUUUCCCCAAUCUCUAUAGGACUCAUGAGAGAUUGCUUGUGUAAAUAUAAAAGCACCAUAUGUGUUCUUAACUCCUAUGGCUGCUUGAAGCUCAUGAUGAAAAAGUCUUUUUGUCAGUUUUAAUUGUUAAGUACAGAACAAACAAUUGUUUGGUGAUGGCCUGGUUGAAAGAGAGCAUAUAAAUAUAUCCCAGUGGAACUCACCAAAGAAGACCACACCUCAGAAAUUAUUGCAUUUUCUCAUUAUGUGUUGGGUUUGAUUUGCUUUUGUUUUUAAUGCAGCUCUUUUAAUAUAAAGAUUCUUGAUACAGUGAAAUCUCUUAUUUCAAGUGUAAGUUAUUCUUCACCCACCCCUUCCCCUGCCAUUGUAUUUCCCAUCUGUUUCAAGGAGUUUCAACAAUUUACAUUGCAUCGUAUGCAGUAGGUACUGCUUUUUCAGAAAGACCUGGAAAACAUACCUGCUAUGAAUAUUUUGUUCAGAUGUAGCCAUUUACCUGGCUCUCAAGUUGUCUUUGUGGAGAGGGUCUUAGACAAAAAUCUUCCUUGUAUUUACUUGGGUUAAGUGAAGUCCAAAUUCUUACAGUAUGCUAUUUCAGGAUUUCUGAUAUUAAAAAAGAAAAAACAAAAUCUUUAUAUCUCUUAUUAACACUUCCCCCAAGAAGGGUUGUGCUGUUAUUUAUUUUCUAUUAUAAGAAAAGUUCAUUCUUUAAGUAGUUUCUUUUACCUCUAAUCUAAUUUCAUACCAAAUACCUGAUCAAUAGAAAUGAUAUAUUUAAGCAGCAAAGAUUCCUAAUCCAUCAUUAUGAAAAGUGUCAGCAUACUUAGUAGUGAACAGAUAAAGUCAAUUUGAAUAUAAUUCCACUUUGUUUUUAGAGACUAAAUUAAGAUUCAAUUAACAUUAUCCUAUGAAUUCUGAAUGUGAUAAUGUGAUUCAAACAGUCAAAUUUUAUUAAGCUCUUAGUAACUCAGGAUAGCAUUCCAUACUAACCUCAAGUUAGCAAAACAAAUUAGUUAAACAGCUUGGUUCUUAGCAGACUGCUUAAAAGAUCAAGAAAAUUUUCUCAUCUUUUCUUUCUACUUAGAAACAUUGCAAGAAACCUUGGACAGUCUUCACCAGACCUGCCAUGAUUUUAUAAGAUUUAGGCCUCAGUGACAUGCUCCUGAAAGUUUCCUGCCAGCCAUCCAAACUAAGCAUCCACUCAUUCCAUCUUCCCAAAGUCACUCACCGAUAAAGGUAGCAUCCUUAAGUUCAUUUUUGAAAGGUGGAGGAGGAUCUCCCCCUGCCCAAAGGAAUUUUUUUAUCAGAAUACCUUGAAAGGGGGGUAUAUAAAUUUGGAAAACUUAAUUUCUUGGCUGUGUUUGAUAACAGUUCCUAUGCAUGGUUUUUAAUGUGAGGUAAAUUUGUUUCUUUCUUCAGAAUACCUCUCUCCACCCCCCACCUUAUUCUUCCUCUUUAAUGAAUAUUUUUAUUGGAGCUCAAACUCCAUGACUUACGUGCUCACUAAGUUUUCUUUUUUCCCCUUGUUUACUCUGUCUGUAUGUAUGUCAAAAGCUGGCAAAACCUCUAAAACUGUCAAGAAAAUGCUUGAAAGUUGAUUUGUCAUAGUGCAAAUUCAUGAUAAAAUGUCUUAAUGUUAUUUGGAUAUGUAGUACAUAGAAACAGAAAAAUAAAGUCAUUUUUAUAACUUAAAA